GUCUGAGAGCUGUGACAUUCAUCUGACUCUAGUGAAAGUCCAACAGCCACUCCCUUUUUGGCCUCCAACUGGGCACCAUGAGGGCCUGCAUCUCCCUGGUAUUGGCCGUGCUGUGUGGCCUGGCCUGGGCUGGAAAAAUAGAAUCCUGUGCAUCUCGAUGUAAUGAGAAAUUUAACCGGGACGCUGCCUGCCAGUGUGACCGCCGGUGUCUCUGGCAUGGGAACUGCUGUGAAGACUAUGAACAUCUGUGUACUGAGGACCACAAAGAGUCAGAGCCAUUGCCACAGCUGGAGGAAGAGACAGAAGAGGCCCUCGCCAGCAACUUGUACUCGGCACCCACCUCCUGCCAGGGCCGCUGCUACGAAGCCUUUGACAAGCACCACCAAUGUCACUGCAAUGCCCGCUGCCAAGAGUUUGGGAACUGCUGCAAGGAUUUUGAGAGCCUGUGUAGUGACCACGAGGUCUCCCACAGCAGUGAUGCCAUAACAAAAGAGGAGAUUCAGAGCAUCUCUGAGAAGAUCUACAGGGCAGACACCAACAAAGCCCAGAAGGAAGACAUCGUUCUCAAUAGCCAAAACUGCAUCUCCCCGUCAGAGACCAGAAACCAAGUGGAUCGCUGCCCAAAGCCACUCUUCACUUAUGUCAAUGAGAAGCUGUUCUCCAAGCCCACCUAUGCAGCCUUCAUCAACCUCCUCAACAACUACCAGCGGGCAACAGGCCAUGGGGAGCACUUCAGUGCCCAGGAGCUGGCCGAGCAGGACGCCUUCCUCAGAGAGAUCAUGAAGACAGCAGUCAUGAAGGAGCUCUACAGCUUCCUCCAUCACCAGAAUCGCUAUGGCUCAGAGCAAGAGUUUGUCGAUGACUUGAAGAACAUGUGGUUUGGGCUCUAUUCAAGAGGCAAUGAAGAGGGGGACUCGAGUGGCUUUGAACAUGUCUUCUCAGGUGAGGUAAAAAAAGGCAAGGUUACUGGCUUCCAUAACUGGAUCCGCUUCUACCUGGAGGAGAAGGAGGGUCUGGUUGACUAUUACAGUCACAUCUACGAUGGGCCUUGGGAUUCUUACCCCGAUGUGCUGGCAAUGCAGUUCAACUGGGACGGCUACUAUAAGGAAGUGGGCUCUGCUUUCAUCGGCAGCAGCCCUGAGUUUGAGUUUGCACUCUACUCCCUGUGCUUCAUCGCCAGGCCAGGCAAAGUGUGCCAGUUAAGCCUGGGAGGAUAUCCCUUAGCUGUCCGGACAUAUACCUGGGACAAGUCCACCUAUGGGAAUGGCAAGAAGUACAUCGCCACAGCCUACAUAGUGUCUUCCACCUAAUAGAACUUCGAGCCAGAAAGGGGCAUGAGGGCUCUUGCGAGACUGAAGUGCUAUCUUCUCUGGACUAGAGAGAAGAGGGAGAGGACUGGAAGGGAUCACCAAAUCUCAAAGCAAUGAGAAGCAUUCCUAAAUCCCAAAGUGCCCACAUGGGAAAGAGAUAAAAUGUACAAAUUAGAAAAAUGUGGAUAAACAGUCAAACCUUUAUCCUCUAGAAUUUUGGCAAUGUUGACUAAGAAACAGAGUCCAAGCAGAGAAGGUAGGAACCCUCCAUAGCUCUCUGCCCUGAUGUGUGGGGGAACUAGGAAGAAGUCCUUUGACCUCACCAGGCCUCAUGCUUCCCUUUAAUGUAAAGGGAAGGGGUUUGCCCACUUUCCUCUUUUUGGGGUUGGUGAGAGGGCAAACCCUGAUAUUUUUACUGUGAAGGUGUUUUCAGUUGUUCUUAGGAAGAACAGCUGAUAGAAAUUCAAGAUUACUAUAAUGGCUGUUAUUAUACACAGCUCUGUAAACUACCACUCAGCCCUGUGUUGGGGUCCUCAAAGAAGUAAGGCCACAGUAAUCAAGCAAGGGCCUUUGGUUUUUUCCAGAGUUAGAUCCUCUCAGAACAGAGUCUGGGAGAACUCCAAUGCUGAAUGGAGAAGGGUAAUAGGUUGGUGCAGUGAAUGGGCUGGGGGUGGGGUGGCCUUCUCCAGGCCUGAGUGUUUUUGUGUCCAGCUCAGUAUCUGCAACAAGAAGUUUCCCACUUGUGGAUGUUUAGUGCAGCCACAGACUUGUAUUUUGAUCCCCAAUUUUUUUUUGAAAGAGUUCUCCUCAUAGGAGGAUGAUUCAGCAUCAGAAGAAGAAGGAACCCAUAGCUUGGUGUCAUUAACAUAAUUAUUUUAAGCCUUAUCCAGCAGCCAUAAUUUGAAUAACUCUACGAGACCAGAGAGACUGUAGUUCCCUAUUUUAACCUCAAUUAUGCAUUUGUCCCCCAACCCCACUGAGAACUAAAUGCUGUACCACAGAGCCGGGUGUGAACUAUGGUUUAGAAGGUUCAAGUUUCCAAUUAAAGUCAUUGAAGAAAACUUGAAA